UUUUUUUUUAAGAUUUUAUUUAUUUUGUUAAAAAAAAAAUCAGUAGCUUUAGGGUUACCCGAGGUGUUGUUCGCAUGGAUGAAUUGUAUAGUGGUGAAGUCUGGGCUUUUAGUGCACCCGUCACCCGAAUAGUGUACAGUGUACCCAAUAGAUGGUUUUUUAAAUCUCCCUCCUUUUUUUUUUCUUUUUAAUUCAAAACUAGAAUGGCCUUGUCUGCUCCUGAGACUCUUCAUAUUCCCCACAGAGCUAAAUCCAAGCUCAGCAUGAUCCACAGUCCAUGUGAUCUAAGUCCUGCCUGCAUCUCUCCAGCUCCCCUACCCAGUGCUUGAACUGUGCAAGUUACCUAAAAUUCUUGCACUUAGCAGCGUAUUUUCUGCCUGUCAGUUUUUGGCUCACACUGCCCUGAUUGUUUAGGAUGUUUGCCAUCCACAUCCUGUCCUCUCACCUUUUCUCCCACUCCAUUUGCCUGAAAACUGGUAUCCUUUAAGUCUUAGCUCAAAAGUCUCUUCUGUGACAGUUUUCCUGACAUCUCCGUCCUCCUGAUAAGGCCAUCACCUCUCCCUCUGAGCUCCCCACGGUACCAUGGUCCCCGUCGUCAUCCCUGCAUUGCUUUCUCGCCCUCCAUUAGCUUCCUGAGGACAGGGGCCAUGUCUAGGUUUGUACUCUUAUCUGCAGGAUCCAGCCGAUGGCCUGGCAUAGAUUCCCAAAAACUGCUCAUUUUGUGAUUGGGGAAAAAAAUUGGCCCUUUCUUGAACACAUGCUGUACCUGUCCUCAUGCUGUACCUCCAGCCUCAGCUGCCUUUGCCCAUGGCCAUCCUCUGUAAGAACUGCCUCCUUCCUAAGGCCCUUCCGAACAUACCUCACAGUCCUUCGUGCAGUCUAGUUUCGUAGGUUCGCAUUAUUGGAGCCUCUGCUUCCCGACCUCAGGGACUCUCUCCCCUCUGACUCUCCAGCCACCAAGAAUACAAGAAAGGCUAGACUGUUGCCUGAAUAAAGUAGGCCCGCCAAGUUCACGUAAGGCUGUUUAACCUGUAGCUACAGUUUCUCUGAACUUUGAGCCACAUGGUAGCUCAGGGCCUGACAGGCAGUACACAGUAAGGGUCCACUGAAAUAGGCCUGGGUGUGAGUCCCAGGUGGUCUGCCCUAGCAAGACCUUGGGCACACAACUUUACCCUGAGCCCCAGUGUCUCUCUCUGAGAGUUGGGAAUACCUUAUGUCAUAGAGGUGUUGUGGGGAUUCAGUCAGGGGAUGUAAAGGGUUGGCACAUUGUGUAUUAGCUGUGUAGCUGAUAUUAUGACUGCAGGCUCCCUGCUUAACUUUCUCUUAGUAGAGCCAUAUUUGAUAAUUUCUAAGGAGUGUUUUUCCCCCCGCCUCCAACAGACUUUCAGGGCAGACAGCUCCUUUCUAAGAAAGUGCCCCUACAGCUCUGGGGGAUAUUCCCUCUAUCAAUUAUCUACUGAAAUAUGACCCAGUCAGUUGUUCAGGGAGAGUAUUCCAUGUAACAAGUAGCAAAAGUGCAGGGAGAAAAGGCCUGCUGCAGCUUGCCUGUGAUGUCAGAGCAAUGGGCUUUAGGGUCCAGAGCAGGAGGUGAGCAGGGCUUCUGGUGGUGCUUGCCAGGCCACACACCCUGCUGAUGGCUCCACAAGGCAAGGGAUGAGCGGGCUUCCAGAUUUCUUCUGGGCCUCAGCUGGAACAGCUGAUGGCUUGGAACAGCUGCUCCAAAGGAGAGCUCCGCUUGACUCAUUGCAUGCGAUCCUAUUCAUUUGCCCUAACUCUCCCCAUGUUAGGAAUCAACCGUCUUCCCAGUAAGGAAACAGGCUCAAGUUUUACUCAAGGUCACAGCUUAAAGGCCUGAGCAAGGUAUCAGGUGUUUCGAUUGCAGAAGGUGGAGGCUGCCAGCUCUUGCAGGUUGAAAAUGAGGAGCUAAGUAGAUUUUUUUUGUUUGUUUCAAAAGACCAUUACUUGAACCUUGGGAGCAGUGGUCCUCAAGGUGUGGUCUUGGGACCGGCAGCAUCAGUAACACCUGGGAAUUUAUUAGAAAGAAAUUCUUGAACUCCACCCCAGACUAACAGGGACCUACUGAAUCAAACUCUGAGGUGGAGCCCGGCAGUCUGUUCUAAUGGCUGGCACAGGGUCAGAACCACUUAGCCAGUGCUCUCAUCAAUUAAGAUCUAGCAUAGUGCCUGGGAUGUGGUCAGUGCUUCGUAAUAAGCAUUUCUUCUGCAUUCUUAGGGCAUAGUACUAUAGUAUAUCGGAAGAUCAUAGUCUGGGAAGGUAGUAGACGUCAGAGCUUCAAAUUCUGGCUUUCCCACCUUUAUAAAUGUAAACUAUUCACCUAAUGUCUUUCUUUGUUGUCUCUAUGGAUAAUACCUAUCUAGCUGGGUGGAGAUGACCAACUCCUCCCUUCAAUGAUUUCCUCACUUACCAGAUUAAUGUUAUUUCAGUAACUUCCUCCCCAAAGGAGUAAGUUUAGGUGUGUGACUCCCCUGCCCUGCCUAAGUGCUUCUGUACUGUACCUCUCUUGAACAGGUGGAGGAAGGAGAGGCCAGUCUACCCUCCCCUGCCAUGACCCUGUCAUCAGCCAUUGACAGUGUGGACAAGGUCCCAGUGGUGAAGGCUAAAGCUACCCAUGUCAUCAUGAAUUCUCUGAUCACAAAACAGACCCAGGAAAGCAUUCAGCAUUUUGAGCGACAGGCAGGGCUGAGAGAUGCUGGCUACACACCCCACAAGGGCCUCACCACCGAGGAGACCAAGUACCUUCGAGUGGCCGAAGCACUCCACAAACUAAAGUUACAGAGUGGAGAGGUAACAAAAGAAGAGAGGCAGCCUGCAUCAGCCCAGUCCACCCCAAGCACCACUCCGCACUCUUCACCUAAGCAGAGGCCCAGGGGCUGGUUCACUUCUGGUUCUUCCACAGCCUUACCUGGCCCAAAUCCUAGCACCAUGGACUCUGGAAGUGGGGAUAAGGACAGAAACUUGUCAGAUAAGUGGAGCCUCUUUGGACCGAGAUCCCUUCAGAAGUACGAUUCUGGAAGUUUUGCCACCCAGGCCUACCGAGGAGCCCAGAAGCCCUCUCCAUUGGAACUGAUACGUGCCCAGGCCAACCGAAUGGCUGAAGAUCCAGCAGCCUUGAAGCCCCCCAAGAUGGACAUCCCAGUGAUGGAAGGAAAGAAACAGCCACCACGGGCCCAUAACCUCAAACCCCGUGACCUGAAUGUGCUCACACCCACUGGCUUCUAGAGCCCUCUUUCCAGGGAUUCUGGUAAAGGUGGUUUCUUGCAUCCCACUCCCCUUUUACCUUGGCUUUGACAUAGGAAAGGUAUAUUUAAAAACUUAAUCAGCUGGGCGUGGUGGCUCACGCCUGUAAUCCCAGCACUUUGGGAGGCCAAGGUAGGUGGAUACCUGAGGUCAGGAGUUCAAGACCAGCCUGGCCAACAUGGUGAAACCCCGUCUCUACUAAAAAUACAAAAAUUAGCUGGGCGUGGUGGUGGGCGCCUGUAGUCCCAGCUACUUGGGAGGCUGAGGCAGGAGAAUCGCCUGAACCCAGGAAGCAGAUGUUGUACCGAGCUGAGAUCAUGCCAUUACACUCCAGCCUGGGCGACAGAACGAGACGCCAUCAAUAAAUAAAUAAAUAAAGUAAAGUAAAAAACCUAUUAAAUUGAGGCUAGAGCUGGAGAUGUAAUUGGUUUUUGAGAAACAUUAGUAUAAAGCUUGCCCUUGUUGUGUGGAAGAAGCCAUUUUGUACUGCUUUAAAGUUAGACUAAUAUUCUCAGCACGGGUGUAUGGGGACCUCAUUACCUAUUUUUUUCAUCAUUUACCCUAGGUAAGAACUUUGAUCACUGCUUACUAGGUAAAGAAUGUUUGUACUGUUCCAAAACCCAGGCUUCUUUAUUCCUUUACCACUAUCCAUGUGAGCAUUGACAAAUCAUGGCUUAGAGGUGCUCACUGACUCGCUAAGACGACUUUGGCCCUGUUGAUGACUGGUGCUGUGCUCCAGCCUUAUCAGUUAGGGGACCCAAGGUUUGUUUGGGACCUGGGUACAGGUAAAAGCCAGACUUGGCAGGGACCCCUCUUUCUAGGCUGAACCUUGAGUCCCCCUGCUUUUUGGCAGACCUAAUGGAUCACUGUCUUGCAGCUAGUUCUUCAUGUGGGGCCUCUUAGGCCAGUGCCGGAGGAGGCAUGCUCCUCUUUCUAUGCCACAGAACAAACACUACUCUAGCAGAGCCUUUCUUGCACUUUAAAGUGAGAUUAAUUUAGCUGUAAUUUGGUUAAAAACUUCCUAAGAGAGAAAAUUAAGUCUACUGAUUUGGUAUAGGUAAAUGGACAUUAAACUUUUUUAAAGUAAAGGAGAUGGUAGAUACCGUUAGAUUAUAGUCUUGAGGUUCAUGUGAAGCCAGUGGUGUUAACUUACUUUGAUUUCCUUGUUCAGGUCAGGGCCUGGAACGCCUGUGCGGGGAGGUCACUCAAUUCAAAAUUUUCUGUAUGAAAGCAUUUUUCACCAAAAUGAGCCUCAUCCCUUUAUGCAACACAUAACCUUACUGAGGGAGGGAAAUACAGAAGCCACCUUUUUAUUUCUCUUCACUGUGUACAAGUUCACUUGUUGUCUUGAACACUGUCUCAAAUACCUGCUUUUUGUUUUGGAUAGUACCUUGUCUGUAUAAGAAGCUGGCCUUUCCAUAGAGAGGCCCUGGAGUCUAAAAUUAUGAGAACAAUUAAUUUAUUUGUGUCUUCUAUUAUGAUCUCGUUUUGACAAUAAAAAUCCUUACUACUUUCUCAAAU